AUUUUCAUGGCGCCGCCCCACCCGCAUUAUCACUGUGUGAUGGUCUCAGUCAGUCUCCUCCCUGUCUCCACUCUUUCCCUCUAUUUAUUUCACUCUCUUGUUUGGUUCUACCCUGCACCCUCGGUCCCCUUCCAGGUUCCUGUUUAUAAGCCCCAACCCCUCUGUCCCCAUCUUGUAUGUGAAAACUUGUCUCAAUAAACCCUUUGGAGUAAGAUGGGUGACGGUGCCAUCUGUUGAGGGCACUGGGGACUUUGGGGGAGGAGUGACCGGCUCUGCCUGGGUUGGGUGGAGUUUGGAGAGAGGGGAUAUGAUGGGUUGGGGUUUUGUGGUAGGGCAGCAGGGGCCGGAGACGGGCCCAGAGCUUGGGUGGGGUGUGGGUGGAGAGAAGUGGAGGCACUGGACCGAAUCUCCUUGUGCCCUUUCUGUCCCUAAGUGCUCCCUCCCCAGGGGUAGAGCCCUGGGGAGCAGAUACUAUGAUGACAGUCCAGCUGAAGCCUCAGCCCCGCCUGGGAUGUGUGAGGGUGGUGGCGAGGCCAAAGGGCUGGUGCCCAGAGGACGUAAACCCCCUUCCUGUUCCCAUCCCAGGCCCACAAGGAGCAGGGAGGGAAAAGGCUGCACCUGCCAGUGGAGGAUGAUGGCUUUGGGGCGCAGGCUCCUCCAUGCUGGGAGGAGGUGCCGCAGGUGCCCGAGCCCUCGUGGCUCAUGUCCUGAUGCGUCCCUCCUUUCCCUUCUCAGUGGUCCACGUCUACUGUACUGAGUGCUUUACAUGGCAUUUCACUGGGUCCACAGCCUUAAAAAGAGGGAGCAGGUGUCCACAUGCUCCAGAUGAGACGGAGGGGACCGCUGCUCCUGUCUCGAGGAGGCUUCCACCACCUACCAGCCAGGCGUCCUCGGUAAUCCUAGCACCUCUGCCACAGGGCACUAAUGCCCAGUUCCUGGGUUGUAAAGGGCUGUGCCCCAGUCCCCCAGCAGGCCCCAGUGAACAUACGAGAAAGGAUGGAGGCCGCUGUCUGGACACUCAGGACAUGGCAGCGUUUUGCUGGGACAGUCAUCUGCCCUUCAGGAAAAAGGGUGCAGCCCCAGCCCCCGGAUGUGGUGACAGAAUCGAUACUGUACCGACCUCAGCUACCCCCAACGGCCGUACACCAGGAAGAGGGGCUCUUCUGGCAGCCCCCAUCCUCAGCCAGCCCUGCCAUUUCCAGUCCUGCCAGCAUCCCAGCCAGACAGGCACCAGUAUACCAUGGCAUCGGCUCCCACCAUCCCAUGUGGGGUCAGUCCUAUUACAGUCCCAACAGAUGGAGGGACUGAGGCUCACAGAGAAGCCACUCACCCAAAGUCACAUGGAGAGAAAGACACGCACACGUACUCCACAUCCCCAGGAGACACACUCUGCAUCUAUGAAGUGGCUCCGCCCCUCUCUGACGUCGCCGAGGCCCGCGCCGAUUGGUCGACUGCACUGUCGCUCCGGACACUUCCUCCUGGGCCGCCGCCGCCGCCGCCGACUUAAACUUUGGAGGGGGAAAAAGAGCUACUGGCGCCUGGCGACCCUCCCUGCCCCCCACCCAACCCCGCUCCGGCAACGCCCCCUUCCUCACGGCUCCCGACCGAACUUUUCUCCAACUUCUGCGACUCGUGAGAUUCCCUUCUACCCACUCCGGCCCUCGGGACCCCUCUGCCCAUCCCCUGGCCGGUCGGGUCCCUGCGAACCCCUUUAUCUCUGGAAUCCACUCGGUCCCCGACUCAGAGACUCCUGCCCUCCACCCCCAAGGUGAAUUCCCCCGGGCCGCCUUCUGAGUGGGAUCCUCUUCUUGGAGCACUGGAUCCUGGGAUUCCCUCUGCCCCCUUCUCAAUCCCUCCUCUAGGGAAGGGGCCUUUGAAUCGCGGGCUCUCCUGAUCCCUGUGACCCCGACCUACUAGAUUUCCUCUCAGGCUUCUUGGAAUCUCAAUCGCUGGGACCUCCAACCCACUACUUUUCUCCUUUCUGAUCUUCUGGGAGCCCUGGAUUCCGGGCCUCUGACCCACUAUAGUGCCUUUCUCUCCUUCCCAGGA